AAUCCCGGGAGCGAAGUUAGAGCUUGAAGGACGGCGGCGGCUGCGGGCGCAGCCCCGGAACCGAGGCCGGGCGGGCAGGUAAGCGGCGAGCGCGGCCGGGCGCUGAACCUGGGGGACUUGGGACCCGGACCACCCCCGGGGAGCGGCGCGGCCAAGCCCCCCGCCACCUCGAACCCCGGGCGUCCCCGAGUGCGCAGCGUGCGCCCCCAGCCCCUGCUGCGCCCCCAGGCCUGGCGCGCGAUCCGAGCGCAGCGGGCAAAGUUGGAGGAACUUGGCGGCGGCGGAGCGGGCGCAGGCUCAGCCCGACAAAGCCCGGGGGCCCGGGUCGGGGUCGCUGCCGCAGCCCGCACGCUGCCCCGUGCCUCCGAGAGGUCCCUUCCCCAGCGCCUCUCUCCCUUCCGUCCCCCUUCGCCGUCCGCACCCUGCCCGGCGCCCCCCAGACGCGGCCCCCUGCCCUUCCCUUCCCGGAAAUUAGGGGGCUGUCCUCACCUCCUGGCCGAGUCGCUGACCCCUCCCCAGGCUCGCAUCGCCCUCCCUGCUGGGCCGCCCUCCCCCCGACGCUGCGAGCCUCCUCGCUCCGCGCGGGGACCGUCCAGUCACGCACGGGGAGGGGUCACAUUCCUCGGUCCCAGCCCCUGAGUCCAACCACUGGCGGGGGGGUGGGGUGGGGGGCUUCGCUCCGAACUGAACUUACUGGGUGCUUUCCACCCCUCGCCCCACCUGGAGUCCAUCCUCGUCCUCGUCCCUCUGGGGGCUGGGAGGAGGCUGCCAAGCCUCCGUGCCCCAACCUGCCUCUAAAGACAAGCGCCCCCAUUUCCAUCCUUUGAAACCUGCAGGUCACCUGCUUGAUGCUGAGGGUGGGGCGGGGGGCACUGCCUGCCGUACCGCACACCGCCCCCCCCCCCAUAAAAACGACACCCUCUGAGAUGAAAAUCCGGCUUUUCCAGGUCUCAGCUGUGUGACCUUGGGGCAGGUGAAUCUCAGAGCCUCAGUUUCCACACCUGUGAAAUGGGGCUAGGAUGAUCAUGCCUUCUGAAAAAAACGAAGGCUUAGCAGAAAGGGUCGAGGCCGGCCGAGCCAGGUGUGCACGUCCUCAAAAAGCCUCCGUGCCAGCACUUUCCCUUCCUGCACACCCGGAGUGGGGCCUCUUUGGACCCUGGCUUGGGCUGGCUGCCUCUGCCGCUCAUUCCCUCGAUUGGGCUAAGGGCUGUGCGGAGAGCCUGGGGACAGAAGCUGUGGAGGGACCGGGAGCCAGGAGCAGAUGUAAAUGGCAAAUCUCCCCAUAUUGCCUCUCUCAGGGGCUGCCCCCUAGAGAGGCCCCCAGCCUCCAAAGAGGUCCAGCUUGCACCCAGCCUUGGGGGAAACCCCAUUGGGUUGGGCAUAGGUUGCUUGAAAAGCAUCAACAUGCUCCUCUUCUCUGCCUGGCUGGCCCCCUGGCCUCCUGCCCCCUGGGUCCCUGCCCCUGCCACCUUUUAAUUGAACAAGCAUUGAGAAGACUGGCUUACAGGUCCCAGCCCAGGUUUGCGCCCCACUCCACCAAAGCAGGGGGACAAACUCCAGGGGGCCGUGUGUGGGAGGGGGUCACCCCCUCACCUGGAUUUGAGGGGGUUUGGAGCCCAGCCAGGACCCCAGCACUUGGGUCCCUCAUUUUCCUGGGCAUACGGUGGUCAGGGAGUUCUGAUCCCCACCCCUAGUGGGCAGAAGACCUGGGGGUCUCCAAGUCAGAGAUUGGGGGCCAUGCCCCUCCCCCUGUCCUACAGCCAGCUGUGCAGCCCCCUCCUCCUCGGCCGCAGCAGGACUGCUGUGUGCGUAUAAUUCAGGAUGAUACAGCAGGCUCGGCAGGCAGCUCCCGACUCCCAGAAAAGCCAGUGGGCACCUGAACCAGAGCCACACUCCUGAGGCCUGAGACAGAGUCUCCCUGUGUUGCCCAGACGGGUCUCAAAUUCCUGGACUUAAGCGAUUCUCCUACGUUGGUCUCCCAAAGUGCUGGGAUUACAGGUGCAGCUGCCUUGGCGACCAUUUGUCCUACAGUUUGUCCGGACCCAGGCUGUCCUUCUGUGUGCUGGAAUGAGGCGAACAUGUCUUUGAGCCCAGCAGGGAGGAAUCCUCCAGCCUAUUCCUCGCUGGUGCAUCAGGUCGUUGGCGGGCCCUGACACACAACAGGAACGUCGGAGCAGGAGGAGUCAGUGGAGCCAUCAGGACACCCAGGCCCAUGGGGCAGGAGGCCUCGGUCACCACAGGACUGGGGCGGAAGACGAGAGGCGGCCGGCCGUGAGGGAGGCGCCCUCCCUCCCCGCGCUUACGUCGCGCGGCCAUGCGGUUUGGGACAGGACACCCCUGAGAGUGCAGGCACCUCCCCCUCCCGCCCCUCCAUCCCUCUGGGGGCUGGCGCCUGGCCCCCCACCUGGUCCCCCUGGGCAGGCUGAAUUGGGGCUCCCUGCAGGGCGGUCCCGAUGGCCGGGCGUGGGUGGGGCGCGCUGUGGGUGUGCGUGGCGGCCGCCACCCUGCUGCACGCUGGCGGCCUGGCCCGCGCAGACUGCUGGCUGAUCGAGGGCGACAAGGGCUUCGUGUGGCUGGCCAUCUGCAGCCAGAACCAACCCCCCUACGAGGCCAUCCCACAGCAGAUCAACAGCACCAUCGUGGACCUGCGGCUCAACGAGAACCGUAUCCGCAGCGUGCAGUACGCCUCGCUCAGCCGCUUUGGCAACCUCACGUACCUCAACCUCACCAAGAACGAGAUCGGCUACAUCGAGGACGGCGCCUUCUCGGGCCAGUUCAACCUGCAGGUGCUGCAGCUGGGCUACAACCGGCUGCGCAACCUCACGGAGGGCAUGCUGCGCGGCCUGGGCAAGCUGGAGUACCUGUACCUGCAGGCCAACCUCAUCGAGGUGGUCAUGGCCAGCAGCUUCUGGGAGUGUCCCAACAUCGUCAACAUCGACCUGUCCAUGAACCGCAUCCAGCAGCUCAACAGCGGCACCUUCGCCGGCCUGGCCAAGCUGUCGGUGUGCGAGCUCUACAGCAACCCCUUCUACUGCUCCUGCGAGCUGCUGGGCUUCCUGCGCUGGCUGGCCGCCUUCACCAACGCCACACAGACGUACGACCGCAUGCAGUGCGAGUCGCCGCCCGUCUACUCCGGCUACUACCUCCUGGGCCAGGGCCGCCGCGGCCACCGCAGCAUCCUCAGCAAACUGCAGUCAGUCUGCACCGAGGACUCGUACGCGGCUGAGGUGGUCGGGCCCCCACGUCCAGCAUCCGGGCGCUCACAGCCGGGCCGCUCCCCGCCGCCCCCGCCUCCGCCGGAGCCCAGUGACAUGCCCUGUGCCGAUGAUGAGUGCUUCUCCGGGGACGGCACCACGCCACUGGUGGCCCUGCCCACGCUGGCCACGCAGGCCGAGGCCCGCCCCCUCAUCAAGGUCAAGCAGCUCACUCAGAACUCGGCCACCAUCACCGUCCAGCUGCCCAGCCCGUUCCACCGGAUGUACACCCUGGAGCAUUUCAACAACAGCAAGGCCUCCACCGUGUCCAGGCUGACCAAGGCCCAGGAGGAGAUCCGUCUGACCAACCUGUUCACGCUCACCAACUACACCUACUGCGUGGUGUCCACCAGCGCCGGGCUGCGCCACAACCACACCUGCCUCACCAUCUGCUUGCCCCGGCUGCCCAGCCCGCCUGGUCCGGUGCCCAGCCCCUCCACGGCCACCCACUACAUCAUGACCAUCCUGGGCUGCCUCUUCGGCAUGGUGCUGGUGCUGGGCGCCGUCUACUACUGCCUGCGCAGGCGGCGGCGCCAGGAGGAGAAGCACAAGAAGGCCGCCUCGGCAGCCGCAGCUGGCAGCCUCAAGAAGACCAUCAUCGAGCUCAAGUACGGGCCAGAGCUGGAGGCGCCCGGCCUGGCCCCGCUGUCCCAGGGCCCGCUGCUGGGCCCCGAGGCCGUGACGCGCAUCCCUUACCUGCCUGCGGCCGGCGAGGUGGAGCAGUACAAGCUGGUGGAGAGCGCGGACACCCCCAAGGCCAGCAAGGGCAGCUACAUGGAGGUUCGAACCGGGGACCCUCCGGAACGCAGGGACUGUGAGCUGGGCCGGCCGGGCCCCGACAGCCAGAGUUCGGUGGCCGAGAUCUCCACCAUCGCCAAGGAGGUGGACAAGGUCAACCAGAUCAUCAACAACUGCAUCGACGCGCUCAAGUCCGAGUCCACCUCCUUCCAGGGCGUCAAGUCGGGGCCCGUGUCCGUCGCGGAGCCGCCGCUGGUGCUGCUGUCCGAGCCGCUGGCCGCCAAGCACGGCUUCCUGGCGCCCGGGUACAAGGACGCCUUCGGCCACAGCCUGCAGCGGCACCACAGCGUGGAGGCCGCCGGGCCCCCUCGUGCCAGCACCUCGUCCAGCGGCUCCGUGCGCAGCCCCCGCGCCUUCCGAGCCGAGGCCGUCGGGGUGCACAAGGCCGCGGCCGCCGAGGCCAAGUACAUCGAGAAGGGCUCCCCCGCGGCCGACGCCAUCCUCACUGUGACACCCGCGGCCGCCGUGCUGCGGGCCGAGGCCGAGAAGGGUCGCCAGUACGGCGAGCACCGGCACUCGUACCCCGGCUCCCACCCGGCCGAGCCACCUGCGCCCCCCGGGCCACCGCCGCCGCCUCCGCACGAGGGCCUGGGGCGCAAGGCGUCCAUCCUGGAGCCACUCACCCGGCCGCGGCCCCGCGACCUCGCCUACUCGCAGCUGUCCCCGCAGUACCACAGCCUGAGCUACUCCUCCAGCCCCGAGUACACCUGCCGGGCCUCCCAGAGCAUCUGGGAGCGCUUCAGACUGAGCCGCCGGCGGCACAAGGAGGAAGAGGAGUUCAUGGCCGCGGGCCAUGCCCUGCGCAAGAAGGUUCAGUUCGCCAAAGACGAGGAUCUGCACGACAUCCUGGACUACUGGAAGGGCGUGUCGGCCCAGCACAAGUCCUGAGCCCCCCAAGACCGGCGAUGCCCACUGGACCAAAAAGGAUGCAGGAUCCACCCAGAGACUCAGCACCAAACCCAACACACGCACGCCACCACAGCAACUGUGACAGCGGGGGGCCCUGCAGAGGCGAGGGGGGAGCGAGUGGGGACAGACAAGGGGGACACGUCCCGAGCUCCUGUGGCCGGUCCUGGGAUGCGCUUGUCGCCCCGGGUGGCACGUGUCCACACACACACACACACACACACACACACACACGAGGGACUUCGGAAAACUGUGUCUUAGGGAUGGGGGGUGGGGGUGGGGAUUUUUUUUUCAUUAUCUUUCCUCUUUUGAGUCUUCUCUGCCUUUUCUUUUCCUCUCUAUCUCUUUACUUUCUUCCUUUUUUAAAAAAAUAUAAUAAAAGACAAGUUAUUUUAAAAAGACAUAAAAUGCCAUCCGUGGGGGGUGUGGCCGGCGUGGCCACCUCGGGGCCCCUCACGUGAUCUCCUCGGUCCGUGGUUUUCUGUGGAUUCUCUGUCCAGUCCGUCUCUUCAUUGCCGCCUCCGGAGUCCACUGCAGAGGGGCAGAGUGAAUGCCGGCGGCCAAGUGGCCUCCGGGACAGGUCCUGGAGCCCUGCUGGACUCAGGGUGGGUGGAGGCUGUGCCUGUGGACGGCCGGGGUGGCCAGGACGGCCAAGGGCUGGGAGGCACGUCCCCCAGCCCAGCCCCCAUGUACACUGUAGUCGUUCUAUUGUACAGAAAAAAAUAUUUCUAUAUUUGCAAUGUUUGCUGUAAAAUGAGAAAGAAAAAAAGACUAUGUCUACUAAAAAAAAAAAAAAAAAGACUAUGUCUACUUAAAAAAAAAUCUGCAAAGGAAAACAAAUCAAA